GGACUCAGGGUCCGUCUGCUCCGGGAACGGACGUCGUCGCAGCCGAGUGAAUUUCGUGUACAUAAGCGUGGAAAACGCUCUUGCAGAUCUCGCGGCAGCCACGCGCAGCGGGGACGUUUUGCCGGGGGUUGAGCUCCCCGCCCCUCUGCCCCGCAGGGGCCGGACACAGGCGCAGACUCCCUCCUGAGCGUGGGUUCCUCCGCGUGAAACGGGCACGAAGCCCACCCCGGCGCUGUCGCCAAAACUGAGAUCUGAGCGCCUUCAGGGGGCCGGGGCCUGGCGGAGACCGGGCCCGCAGCGGGAGCGCGAGCGACGGCCGCCCUCCCAGGCACCGGGAGGCUGUGGCGCCCACCGAGCUCCGCGGAGCCGUGAAGGAGAGUCCAGGUUCCACAGUGUCCCUUCUUAUCCCAGGCGGGUGGGCUCCCCGGGCCUCCCCGCCUCUCCAGCCCGCCGCCCUCCCGCAGGCUGUGCCGCGCCAAGCCCCCUACACACACCCUCUCUCUUUUCGGUCUCCGCUGCUGAAAUUUUCUCUAGAAAUUUCUUUCCCGCUGCCCAGCAAACUCUUGCUCUUCCUUGAAGGCUUCUUCCUCCACCACCUCCUCCAGGAAGCCCUCCCUCCUCAGCCCAGCUGGAGGAGAUCGCUCCAUCUUUCCUGCCGCUCCCACUCCUAGCUUUGGGUCUCACCAGGGGUGCCUGGUGGUGCAGCCGUGAGCAGAGCUCCUGUUCCCACAAGCCGGGCCGAGCUCCCAAGGCCAUGGCUACCACAGCUCUCUUGCCGCUGGCCAAGUUGGUCAGCCCUAGGGCGAGGGUUCCAGUGCCUUGAUCCAACCCCCAGCUGGUUCGGUGGCAGAGGAGGACAAGGGUCACAGCACACACACAAUCCUGAGCCUGGGAUUCCUCUCUGAGAAAGGGGGUGGUGCUGAGGCCACAGAAGCAGCUGCCCAGAGCCUUUUUGAAGGGGUUGAGCUCUGGGCCUGGUCUGGGUCCUGGGUCUGGGGAGGACCUGGGGAGGUGCGGGUGACGGCACCGCAGGUAAGGCUCCUGCAAGGUGGCAGCCUUGGGGCCCGACCCUGGGUAGGAGGGCAGGCCAGUGAUGACAAGGGAGGCCCCAGCCAGGCGAAGUUGCAGGCAGGGGCAGUGCAGGGUCCCAGCAGGUGAAGGCCCCGGGAGUGGAGUCUGCAGGGCCCUGGGCCAGAGUGUUCAGGGCACAGGUGACUAAGCCCAGCCAGGUCUUCAGCUCAAGGCCUAGGGGAAGUGGGGCUGGGCCCUGGUGAGCAGAUCCCUGGGCCCUUCCUGAGGUCUGGCCAGGCCGACCCCACCUGGAGGUGGCGGCUCAGGGCAUUUGACGCCUCCUUCCCAGUUCCCUGGCUCGGCAAGCAGCUGACCCUCAGGUGGACAGCAGCUAGACCAGGCCCCUGAGUGACACGGCUGGGUGGGGGUGUCCCACAGAGCCCACCUCCCAUCUCGCUCCAGGCUAGAGCUCAGGGUCAGUCACAGGCUGCCACCCUAGAGAAGAGAGCACCUUUCAGGGGCAGCUGAAUGGAGACCCCUCAACAGGGAAAGCCGGAAAUGACCCAGCGGCAGCCAUAUCUCUAGGACCGCCCCCGGGUGAAGGACAGACAACUGCACACCACAGAGCUCGGGAAAACCAACAGCAUCUCAGUGUAGCGGGGAGAUGGGCAGAUGGGGGAUCCAGGCUGGGCCAGCCUUGUCCACAGCCCAUAGAAGGGUUGGCCAGCCAGAAGGGUGCAUCGGGGUGCCCAGAGGGUCAGAAGGCCAGGCUGGGGCCCCAAGUCCCAGGGGAGGCCUGGGAAAGCCCCGGGGGAGGCCAUGGUUCCACUCGGUGGCCGGGCCAAGCAGGUUGUGCCCAGCUGGCUCUAGAGCGUGCAGAAGGGGCCUGUGUCGUGGCGCUUGGGUCUGCGUACACCCUGGAUGACCACGCCAGGCGCCGAAGGGAAGCGUGAGUUGCAGUCCUCCACGUGGUAGGCGGCUGGGCCAGGGGUUCGGGCUGCCGAAAGAGAAGGCUGGGAGCCCCACCCAGGUAGCAGCCCCAACUCAAACCUGGCUCCCAGUUCCCACCCCCGGCCCCUGAACCCUUGUCCUCACAUUGCCCACCCAUGCCCCAUCCCUAGCCCUCUUCUCUCCAGGCCUCCUUACAGGUGCUGAGCCAGGAGGUGAACGCAGGGGAGCGGCUCAUCGAGAAGGCCGGCGAGCGGGGGCUCUGCAGGCGGCUCCCAGGAAGGAUAUUGUAGGUGUUGGGGCCAGGGCAUCUCUUGCCAGGUGCCUGCAAAGAGGCCUGAAGCAGGGACUGGGGCUGCACCCUGAGGCCCAGCCCCCUAGCCCCAGGCAGCCCUAGGUGGGUGUGGCCUUCAGGUGUCUUGGAAGCGGAGUGGCAGCCUCUGAAGCUGAAGGCGGGGAAGGCGGGCCGGCUGAGCAGCUGGUAGUGGGCUGGCGAGGGCCACUGCGAGGGGGUAGGAGACGGGCUGCAGGGCAGGGUGCUCCCCACGGACCCUCAGCCAGCCCCCCUUUGGCCCCACUGGAACCCCCAGCCCCCUGCCUGCGUGGACUCCCCGCCCCCUUCCUGCCCAGCCCCCAACCUUUUGCUCUUGGUCGAAGUCAGCUUUCUGCGUGAAGGGGCUUUCGCUCUGGAACCACAAAGUCUGCCAUGCCCUGCGGCCACCGCCCUCUGUAGUUGGAGGAUGGAGAGAGAGAAGGCUGGGAGCCCCACCCAGGUGACAGUCCCCACUCGAACCUGUCUCCCGGUUCCCACCCUCGGCCCCUGAACCCUUGUCUUCACAAUGUCCACCCAUGCCCCAGCCCUAGCCCUCCUCUCUCCAGGCCUCCUUACAGGUGCUGAGCCUAGAGGUGAACGCAGGGAAGGGUGGAGGGGCCCUCAGGCCGUGGGGGUUUCAGCACAGAGGCAAAGGCCCCCAUUCCCAGGGUGAGGGACAGGCCCGGUGGUUGGGCCUCAGGGAGGGGACACACACCUCGGCCCUGGUGCUUGCAGCCGAUGCUGUAGUGGGGGUGUGGGGAGGACUCUCGUACGGACGGGCUCGGCACCUGGUACCUGGUGGGGCUGGGGACUUCCAGGUCAGCUGUGAUCAGGGGGCGUUGCUCCAGCACUGGCCACAGGAAGCAAGCUCUGGGCCUGGGCUCCUUUCAGCGGGCCCCUCCCACAGCCCCCCAAAGACCAGCUUGGGGGUGGGGUGGCCAGGACCCUCACUCACAUAGUUCCCUCAGGGUCUGGGUGUAGGUGGGCAGGGACUCCUGGGGGGUGCCCGUCUGUAACCUGAGGCCAACUGGGAUCUCCUUCAUCUUUGGGGGCUGUGUCUCAUCCCAGGCCAUCCCCGGCUCCGGGCCCAACAACAGCACAGAUGCCUUGGGCCUGCAAGGGAGACCAGCAGCCACUGUCUCAGCCCCCGGCCGCUCCCAGCCACAUGCCCCACAGCCUGUCCCCUCUAUUGUCCCUCAGCCCCCGGCUGCUCCCAGCCACGUGCCCCACAGCCUGUCCCCACACUGUCCCUCAGCCCCUGGCCGCUCCCAGCCGCCUGUCCCCUCUACUGUCCCUCAGCCCCUGGCCGCUCCCAGCCGCCUGCCCCACAGCCUGUCCCCACACUGUCCCUCAGUCCCCCAGCCGCCUGCCCAGCAACCUGCCCCCCACACUGUCCCUCAGCCCCCUGGCCACUCCCAGCUGGCCCGCCCCUUCUCCCCCUCUCCGCCAGUUACUGGGUGGGCUCUGGUUGUGUCUGCCUCAGGUGACCAUGGGUCCAGUGUUUGCCUCCAUUGAUGUAAAAAUUUGCCAGGAAUUUCACUGCCUUCUGGUCAGAAUUCAUCAUCAGAGUCUCCUGGCUCUCUUCCCCAACGGCACCACGGAGCUCUGUGACCUCACUGGUAGGCCCCUCUGUUGCUGGGACUCCUGAGGAAGACACAUUGUCUGGCCCUGGAGGGGCUGCCCCGGGCCCCGACCCCUGGUGGGCCCCUCCCCCACUAACUAGAUGAUCAGCGGGUCCGCCUGGGCCAGGACCCCCAGCCUGCCCCGGUGACUCCUGGCCCAGCCCUCUCCCUCCCCGCAACCUUUCCAGCCUUCUCCCCUCUCCUGCACCCUGGGGUCUCCUGGGAGUCUGGGGUCCACUCUAGCAGGUCUGGGAGGACUGAGGCCUCAGCAGAGGGGGUGGAGGGAACAGGACCCACCGGCAUCCACCAAGCCCUAGGAGAUGCCCAGCUGUGUCUGGCCAGCCAGGACCCCCUGGGGGUAGGAGGGAGGGGCCCAGGAAGGCUCCCUGGAGGAAGAGGAGGAGCCGCCACCCCAUCUGGAUUUCCACUUAAGGGAAAAGCAAAUCCACAUCAGAUGGGUCUGACACCAGAGGCAGGCCGGGCCUUGGAGCCCAGCCAGGGCUGGGGUGUGAGGGCCUACCUCUCACCUGGGGGCACAGAGGCUAGAGGGUGUCACAGAUGGCCGGGCUGCCAGAGCUGCAAAGGAACAGCCAGCCUGUGUGAGCAAGAGCCCGUGUGGGCACCAGGGCCCUCACUGUGUGGUCUCUGGAGCUGACCACCAGUUGGUCCCAGCCCUGACCUUGGCCCAGAAUCCACCAGGGCAGGGCCUGUGAACAGGGCCAACUUGGGGCCCUCCUCCGCCCUCUCUGGAUGCCUCCCCUUCAGCACUGGGCCUGCCAGGCAGACAGAUGGACACGUGCUUGAGGAAACACGGGUUUUAUCUGGGCGAGGGGUUCACGCCUGUGCUCCGGGGCCCCUGCCCAGGUUGUGCCGGGUUCAGAGUUGACUGGCUGCCAGUGGAACAGAGUGUACUUUGCUAAUGAAGCCCUUGUCAUUGGACAGAUAGGCUCCUCCAGGUCCUCCCUGCCCUGUAAUAAACGUUGCCACCGUGAAUGGUGCUGCUGGACAUCCAUCCUCUCCUUGAGAAGGACUCCCCUCAGGGAAGGGAGCUGGAUGCCGGGAGGGACUGGAGCCAGCAAGGCCAGAGUGAAAGCAAAAUGACAACUACUCAGAAACACGAUCUCUUCACGCCGGAGCCUCACUAUGUCCCUGGCUAUGCCGGCUUCUUUCCGCAGCUGCGCUACCAGGUGGGGAACACCUAUGGGCGUACCACGGGGCAGCUGCUCACAGACCCCAGUGUGCAGAAGAGCCCCUGCUCUGUGCUGUCCCCCAUGUCCAAACCCAAGUUCAUUGAGGACUUCAGCCAGUCCAAGCCCCCGAGGGUUCCCUGCCAAGACCUGACGGAGCCCUACAUCCCCCACUACACCAGUCUGAAGCCCUCUAAGAACUUUGAGAUUCUGGGCCAGCUCCCACCCUUGGAGGUGGACGCCCAGGAGCCGCCAGGGGUAGAGAACAUACCCAGACAGAUUCUGCUGCCUGCAGGCUUCACGCCCGACACCCCGCACCCUCCGUGCCCACCAGGCAGGAAGGGAGACUCCAGAGACUUGGGACACCCAGUAUACGGGGAAGAGGCCUGGAAGAGCGCCACUCCUGUUUGCGAGGCCCCCAGGCAGCACCAGCUGUACCACUGCCAGAGGGAUGAGUACCCACCCCCCGCCCGCCGCCAGCAGGAGACGCUAGAUGUGGGCAGCUUCCAGCGGCUGCCGCAGCUGGACCACCCUAACCUAAUCCAACGCAAGGCCAUCUCAGAACAGGCUAGCGGCCUGGGGGGACCUCCUCUGCCUCCCAGCUGCUUCCAGGAGCCCAGCUUUUCCCAAGACGAGGCGGUGCCUUGCCUGCCUGUUCCCAUUUGGCCACAUCAGACAGUCGCCAACGUUCAGGGAACGAAAGGGAGCCUUGCCUGGCUUCCCUGACACGU